AAGUUAACAACUUAAUGCUAGAGUCUGGGAAGGAGCAACUACUUAAAUCUUCCCAAAUCUGGUGCCCAUACCUUCUAUGGCAGGGGCUUUUAGCACCAUUCUUUAACGUUAGACACAUAACCACAGCCUAAUCACUUGAACCAUUUAAUCCUUACCAGCCUCUAGCAUUAUCCUAAAACCCUGAACCUCUUCCAGCUUUCUUAAACUUUCAGCUUUUCUUGAAACGACUUUUUCUGAUUCUAAGAUUAUUUUAACUGUAAGUAGGAGAAGACAUCUGAAAUUUAACUAUGAUCAGAAAUUCAGAUUACAAAAACUUUGUUUGCUGUGCUGUUUGUAAUAAAAUAAUUCCACCAGCCCCUUUUGGAAAAACCUUCAAACGGAUCCAUGAAUACAAGCCACUUAAGACACGCUUUUACACUCACAAAGACAUACUAGAUAUUGGGGCAAAUAUUCUGAAAAAAGAAGAGCAGUUUCAAGAAGAUAUACUCAGAGAACACAUUGCGAAAGCAGAAGCUGAAGUAUGGGCUCAGGCUAAUGAACGUCAAAAACAAGCAGUGGAGAAAGCACUUGAAGAAGCAAAUGACAGACACAAAAUUGAAAUUCAGAUUUUGAAAGAGGAACAUCAGAAAGAUUUACAGGAAGUGACAGCUAAAACUAAGACAGAGAUGUAUCAAAACAUGGAUGACGAAAUGAAGAGAGAGCACUUGGCUGCAGAACAGCGCAUGGUCCACAGAAUCCAAAGGAUUAUGAUGGAAUGCCACAGAGAGAAGGUCGAAGCUGUGGAGAAAGCCAGGGCUGAAGAAAGACACAUCGCCCAGGAAGCAAUCCAGGCCCAGAAAAGCAAAGCCGUGGAGGAAAUUGUGAAUACUGGUGUCACAGUUAUUAAGGAUGAGAAGACCAGUGUGGCCCGACUGAUGAGGGAAAAAGAACAUGAAAUGAGCAUCCUCUAUGGCAUAGCUCAGAGGCAGAGGCAAGAAGAGGUACAGGAAGUGCUUCAAGAAGCAGAGAAAACACAUCAGGCCACUCUUGGCAAUAUGAUGGAUAAACUGGCUAACACCCAGGGGGAGCUGCUGUCUAUAGCAAAACAACUGGGAAUCAUGACAAAUUGGAAAGAUUUCCUAGAGGAGGAAUUACAGGAAACCAGGAUGGCAUUUCAAAAAUACAUCAAUUAUACCUUUCCUAAGCUUUCACCAGGACAUGCAGAUUUUAUUCUGCCAGAAAGAAAGAAAACACCUUCUAAUCUUGUUAUUAAGGAGAACAAAACAACUCUUGAUUAGAAGUCUUCAGUUGAAAUUCCACUACAAAAGACAUCAUUCCAGACUAAAUAAAUUUACUCAAAAACCA